AGCACCAUGAGCCGCCAGCUUCUGCCUGUACUGCUGCUGCUGCUGCUCAGGGCUUCGUGCCCAUGGGGUCAGGAACAGGGAGCGAGGAGCCCCUCGGAGGAGCCUCCAGAGGAGGAAAUCCCCAAGGAGGAUGGGAUCUUGGUGCUGAGCCGCCACACCCUGGGCCUGGCCCUGCGGGAGCACCCUGCCCUGCUGGUGGAAUUCUAUGCCCCGUGGUGUGGGCACUGCCAGGCCCUGGCCCCCGAGUACAGCAAGGCAGCUGCCGUGCUCGCGGCCGAGUCAAUGGUGGUCACGCUGGCCAAGGUGGAUGGGCCCGCGCAGCGCGAGCUGGCUGAGGAGUUUGGUGUGACGGAGUACCCUACGCUCAAGUUCUUCCGCAAUGGGAACCGCACGCACCCGGAGGAGUACACAGGACCACGGGACGCUGAGGGCAUUGCCGAGUGGCUGCGACGGCGGGUGGGGCCCAGUGCCAUGCGGCUGGAGGACGAGGCGGCCGCCCAGGCGCUGAUCGGUGGCCGGGACCUAGUGGUCAUUGGCUUCUUCCAGGACCUGCAGGACGAGGACGUGGCCACCUUCUUGGCCUUGGCCCAGGACGCCCUGGACAUGACCUUUGGCCUCACAGACCGGCCGCGGCUCUUUCAGCAGUUUGGCCUCACCAAGGACACUGUGGUUCUCUUCAAGAAGUUUGAUGAGGGGCGGGCAGACUUCCCCGUGGACGAGGAGCUUGGCCUGGACCUGGGGGAUCUGUCGCGCUUCCUGGUCACACACAGCAUGCGCCUGGUCACGGAGUUCAACAGCCAGACGUCUGCCAAGAUCUUCGCGGCCAGGAUCCUCAACCACCUGCUGCUGUUUGUCAACCAGACGCUGGCUGCGCACCGGGAGCUCCUAGCGGGCUUUGGGGAGGCAGCUCCCCGCUUCCGGGGGCAGGUGCUGUUCGUGGUGGUGGACGUGGCGGCCGACAAUGAGCACGUGCUGCAGUACUUUGGACUCAAGGCUGAGGCAGCCCCCACUCUGCGCUUGGUCAACCUUGAAACCACUAAGAAGUAUGCGCCUGUGGAUGGGGGCCCUGUCACCGCAGCGUCCAUCACUGCUUUCUGCCAUGCAGUCCUCAACGGCCAAGUCAAGCCCUAUCUCCUGAGCCAGGAGAUACCCCCUGAUUGGGAUCAGCGGCCAGUUAAGACCCUCGUGGGCAAGAAUUUUGAGCAGGUGGCUUUUGACGAAACCAAGAAUGUGUUUGUCAAGUUCUAUGCCCCGUGGUGCACCCACUGCAAGGAGAUGGCCCCUGCCUGGGAGGCAUUGGCUGAGAAGUACCAAGACCACGAGGACAUCAUCAUUGCUGAGCUGGAUGCCACGGCCAACGAGCUGGAUGCCUUCGCUGUGCACGGCUUCCCUACUCUCAAGUACUUCCCAGCAGGGCCAGGUCGGAAGGUGAUUGAAUACAAAAGCACCAGGGACCUGGAGACUUUCUCCAAGUUCCUGGACAACGGGGGCGUGCUGCCCACGGAGGAGCCCCCGGAGGAGCCAGCAGCCCCGUUCCCGGAGCCACCGGCCAACUCCACUAUGGGGUCCAAGGAGGAACUGUAGCUGCCCCCGUGUCACCCCCGCCAUCACUGCUGGACAGGAGCCACCCCCUUGGGUACCAGAGGGAGCUGUGCAUUGUGAAUAAAGAGUGAGCUUGGUUCUGGA